AGUCGCGCGCGGUGCAGUCGGGAGGUGGAGGCACCGGCUGCAUUGUUUUCGGGAUCGAGGGGUGAGGGCGCUAUGGCACCCGGCUGCAAAACUGAGUUACGCAGCGUGACAAAUGGUCAGUCUAACCAACCAAGUAAUGAAGGUGAUGCCAUCAAAGUUUUUGUGCGAAUUCGUCCUCCUGCAGAAAGAUCUGGGUCAGCUGAUGGAGAGCAGAACUUAUGCUUAUCUGUGCUGUCCUCCACGAGUCUCCGGCUGCACUCCAACCCUGAGCCCAAGACCUUCACGUUUGAUCAUGUUGCAGAUGUGGAUACCACUCAGGAAUCUGUAUUCGCAACUGUGGCUAAAAGCAUUGUGGAGUCUUGCAUGAGCGGUUAUAAUGGUACCAUCUUUGCAUAUGGACAGACUGGCUCAGGGAAGACAUUUACUAUGAUGGGACCAUCUGAAUCUGAUAAUUUUUCUCAUAACCUGAGAGGAGUAAUCCCACGAAGUUUUGAAUAUUUGUUUUCCUUAAUUGAUCGUGAAAAAGAAAAGGCUGGAGCUGGAAAGAGUUUCCUUUGUAAGUGUUCCUUUAUUGAAAUCUACAACGAGCAGAUAUAUGAUCUACUGGACUCUGCAUCGGCUGGACUGUACUUAAGGGAGCAUAUCAAGAAGGGAGUCUUUGUUGUUGGUGCGGUGGAGCAGGUGGUAACCUCAGCUGCUGAAGCCUAUCAGGUGUUGUCUGGAGGAUGGAGGAAUAGACGUGUGGCAUCAACAUCAAUGAACAGAGAAUCGUCUAGGUCUCAUGCCGUCUUUACAAUUACAAUAGAGUCAAUGGAGAAAAGUAAUGAGAUUGUGAAUAUACGGACCUCCCUACUCAACCUGGUGGAUUUAGCAGGAUCUGAAAGGCAAAAAGAUACCCAUGCAGAAGGGAUGAGAUUGAAGGAAGCAGGUAACAUAAAUCGAUCAUUGAGCUGCCUGGGCCAAGUGAUUACAGCACUUGUCGACGUGGGUAAUGGAAAACAGAGACAUGUUUGCUACAGAGACUCCAAACUUACCUUCUUACUACGGGAUUCCCUUGGAGGUAAUGCCAAAACAGCCAUAAUUGCAAAUGUUCAUCCUGGAUCCAGGUGUUUUGGGGAAACCCUAUCAACACUUAACUUUGCUCAAAGAGCCAAGCUGAUUAAAAACAAGGCAGUAGUAAAUGAAGACACCCAAGGAAAUGUGAGCCAGCUCCAAGCUGAAGUGAAGAGGCUCAAAGAACAACUGGCGGAGCUUGCUUCAGGACAGACACCACCAGAAAGCUUCCUGACCAGAGACAAAAAGAAGACUAACUAUAUGGAGUAUUUCCAGGAAGCAAUGUUAUUCUUUAAGAAAUCUGAACAGGAAAAGAAGUCUCUGAUAGAAAAAGUUACCCAAUUAGAAGACCUCACCCUCAAAAAGGAAAAAUUUAUUCAAUCUAAUAAAAUGAUUGUGAAAUUCCGAGAGGAUCAAAUAAUACGCUUGGAAAAGCUCCACAAGGAAUCCCGGGGAGGUUUUCUGCCUGAGGAGCAGGAUCGUUUGCUCUCAGAAUUAAGGAAUGAGAUUCAAACUCUGCGAGAACAAAUAGAGCACCACCCCAGAGUUGCAAAGUAUGCUAUGGAAAAUCAUUCCCUCAGGGAGGAGAAUAGAAGACUGAGAUUAUUAGAGCCUGUGAAAAGAGCUCAAGAAAUGGAUGCCCAGACCAUUGCAAAACUAGAAAAAGCUUUCUCUGAAAUAAGUGGCAUGGAGAAAAGUGACAAAAAUCAGCAAGGAUUUUCACCUAAAGCUCAGAAAGAGCCAUGUUUGUUUGCAAACACUGAGAAGUUAAAAGCACAACUCCUGCAAAUUCAGACAGAGCUGAAUAAUUCAAAGCAAGAAUAUGAAGAAUUCAAAGAACUUACUAGGAAAAGGCAGCUAGAAUUGGAAUCAGAGCUUCAGUCUUUGCAAAAAGCGAACCUUAAUCUUGAAAACCUUUUGGAAGCAACAAAAGCCUGCAAGCGGCAAGAAGUUUCUCAGCUGAAUAAAAUUCAUGCUGAAACACUUAAGCUCAAGAAUGUUAUGUGGAUAUAUAAUGAUUUAUUCAACCUGGAAAAUGCUGGGUUUUUUCCUAUACAGAUUAUAACUACACCAACCAAGGCCUACCAACUUCAUUCCCGACCAGUACCAAAAUUAAGCCCUGAAAUGGGAAGCUUUGGCUCUCUAUACACUCAGAAUUCUAGCAUAUUAGAUAAUGAUAUAUUAAAUGAGCCAGUUCCUCCUGAGAUGAAUGAACAAGCUUUUGAGGCCAUUUCUGAAGAGCUUAGAACAGUGCAGGAACAAAUGAGUGCUCUUCAAGCCAAACUGGAUGAAGAAGAGCAUAAAAACCUAAAGCUUCAGCAGCAUGUUGACAAACUGGAACAUCAUUCUACCCAAAUGCAGGAGCUUUUCUCAUCAGAAAGAAUUGAUUGGACCAAACAGCAGGAAGAGCUUCUCUCACAGUUGAAUGUCCUUGAAAAGCAGCUUCAAGAGACUCAAACUAAAAAUGACUUUUUGAAAAGUGAGGUACAUGACCUGCGAGUAGUCCUUCAUUCUGCUGACAAGGAGCUUUCUUCAGUGAAAUUGGAAUAUAGUUCAUUCAAAACGAAUCAGGAGAAAGAAUUCAACAAACUUUCCGAAAGACACAUGCAUGUACAGCUUCAAUUAGAUAAUCUCAGGUUAGAAAACGAAAAGCUGCUUGAGAGCAAAGCCUGCCUACAGGAUUCCUAUGACAACUUACAAGAAAUAAUGAAAUUUGAGAUUGACCAACUUUCAAGAAACCUCCAAAACUUCAAAAAAGAAAAUGAAACUCUGAAAUCUGAUCUGAAUAAUUUGAUGGAGCUUCUUGAGGCAGAAAAAGAACGCAAUAACAAAUUAUCAUUACAGUUUGAAGAAGAUAAAGAAAACAGUUCUAAAGAAAUCUUAAAAGUUCUUGAGGCUGUACGUCAGGAGAAACAGAAAGAGACGGCCAAGUGUGAGCAGCAGAUGGCAAAAGUACAGAAACUAGAAGAGAGCUUGCUUGCUACUGAAAAAGUGAUCAGUUCCCUGGAAAAGUCUAGAGAUUCUGAUAAGAAAGUUGUAGCUGACCUCAUGAACCAGAUCCAGGAGCUAAGAACAUCGGUCUGUGAGAAAACAGAAACUAUAGACACCCUGAAACAAGAACUGAAGGACAUAAAUUGCAAAUACAACUCUGCUUUGGUUGACAGAGAAGAGAGCAGAGUGUUGAUCAAGAAGCAGGAAGUGGAUAUUCUGGAUCUGAAAGAAACCCUUAGGCUGAGAAUACUUUCUGAGGACAUAGAGAGGGAUAUGCUCUGUGAGGACCUGGCUCAUGCCACUGAGCAGCUGAACAUGCUCACAGAGGCCUCAAAAAAACACUCGGGGCUGCUGCAGUCUGCCCAGGAAGAACUGACCAAGAAGGAAGCCCUGAUUCAGGAACUUCAGCACAAGCUAAACCAAAAGAAAGAGGAAGUAGAACAGAAGAAGAAUGAAUAUAACUUCAAAAUGAGGCAACUAGAACAUGUGAUGGAUUCUGCUGCUGAGGAUCCCCAGAGUCCUAAGACACCACCUCACUUUCAAACACAUUUGGCAAAACUCCUGGAAACACAAGAACAAGAGAUAGAAGAUGGAAGAGCCUCUAAGACUUCUUUGGAACACCUUGUAACAAAGCUAAAUGAAGACAGAGAAGUCAAAAAUGCUGAAAUCCUCAGAAUGAAGGAGCAGUUGCGUGAAAUGGAAAACCUACGCCUGGAAAGUCAGCAGUUAAUAGAGAAAAACUGGCUCCUGCAAGGUCAGCUGGAUGAUAUUAAAAGACAAAAGGAAAACAGUGAUCAGAAUCAUCCAGAUAAUCAACAGCUGAAGAAUGAACAAGAAGAAAGUAUCAAAGAAAGACUUGCAAAAAGUAAAAUAGUUGAAGAAAUGCUGAAAAUGAAAGCAGACCUAGAAGAAGUCCAAAGUGCCCUUUACAACAAAGAGAUGGAAUGCCUUAGAAUGACUGAUGAAGUCGAACGAACCCAAACUUUGGAGUCUAAAGCAUUCCAGGAAAAAGAACAACUGAGAUCAAAGCUGGAAGAAAUGUAUGAAGAAAGAGAGAGAACAUCCCAGGAGAUGGAAAUGUUAAGGAAGCAGGUGGAGUGUCUUGCUGAGGAAAAUGGAAAGUUGGUAGGUCACCAAAAUUUGCAUCAGAAGAUUCAGUACGUAGUGCGACUAAAGAAGGAAAAUGUCAGGCUUGCUGAGGAGACAGAAAAGUUGCGUGCCGAAAAUGUAUUUUUAAAAGAAAAGAAAAGAAGUGAAUCUUGAGGAUUCCGGUCAGCUACCUAGGCAUCACCUUGUUUGAAGAUGUUUCUUCUCUUUUACAAGUAAGACCUACUCCUGGCCACUUAGGAGAGCUGAAUUUAUGGACCUUAAUUAUUAAAUGUUUAUAAGGUGGUGGUAACCACCUCAAGUUUCUGAUGAACAUUCUGCAUCCAUAUACACCCUGUGACAGUCAGCAGUCUGCUAUUAAGUGGCCUACUUCAAGGCUUUGAAUCAACUUAAGGGAAAACCUUUUGUCUUUGUAAAAAUAAAAGCCUGUAGCUAAGGUUUACAGUGGACAUUAGCCAGAUCAUUUUCUUCUUAGAUUAUGCCAUAAUCUCCUUUGAUUCUUAUGGAAGUUCUAACAAUAUAUGGUGGUUCCAACACCUGCAGUGAGUUUAAUGACUGACUUAGUAGCAGGUACAAGAAGCAAACUUGUUAAUAUAGAUUAUUUUUGUAUUCUUACUUUAGGUAUUUUCUUGAGCAUUUUCCAUGACUGUAAAUAAAGCCAUUUUUUAAGAUAAUAA